AGCUCACUUCCGCCCGGCAGGUGACAGCCGCGGGGCUCCGAGCCGCCGGCAGCCCGGACGCACCGGGAGAGCGAGAGGUGGAGGCCGCGGACAUUUUGGUGCCAAGCCGAACCGAGCCGGGGCGCCGGGAGCUAUUGGGACCUGCGGAAGCCUGGCUACAGAUAAGGGACCAAAAUGACUGACUCAAAAUAUUUCACCACGACCAAGAAAGGGGAGAUCUUCGAGCUGAAGGCAGAGCUCAACAGUGACAAGAAGGAGAAGAAGAAGGAGGCAGUGAAGAAAGUGAUUGCAUCGAUGACCGUGGGCAAAGAUGUCAGUGCCCUCUUCCCCGAUGUGGUCAACUGCAUGCAGACGGACAACCUGGAGCUGAAGAAGCUAGUAUACCUCUACUUGAUGAAUUACGCCAAGAGUCAGCCUGACAUGGCCAUUAUGGCCGUCAACACCUUUGUGAAGGACUGUGAGGACCCCAACCCCCUCAUCCGAGCCCUGGCAGUGCGGACCAUGGGCUGCAUCCGCGUUGACAAGAUCACAGAGUACCUGUGCGAGCCACUCCGGAAGUGCCUGAAGGACGAGGAUCCAUAUGUGCGCAAGACAGCAGCUGUGUGCGUGGCCAAGCUCCACGACAUCAACGCCCAGCUGGUGGAGGACCAGGGCUUCCUGGACACCCUUAAAGACCUCAUCUCCGACUCUAACCCCAUGGUGGUGGCCAAUGCAGUGGCAGCGCUCUCAGAAAUUGCCGAGUCUCACCCCAGCAGCAACCUGCUCGAUCUGAACCCACAGUCCAUCAACAAGCUGCUGACAGCCCUCAAUGAGUGCACCGAGUGGGGCCAGAUCUUCAUCCUGGACUGCCUCGCCAACUAUAUGCCCAAGGACGACCGCGAGGCCCAGAGCAUCUGUGAGCGGGUCACCCCCAGGCUCUCCCAUGCCAACUCCGCUGUGGUGCUCUCUGCUGUGAAGGUGCUGAUGAAGUUCAUGGAGAUGUUGUCUAAGGACUUGGACUACUACGGCACACUGCUCAAGAAGCUGGCCCCACCCCUGGUCACACUGCUGUCAGCCGAGCCAGAGCUGCAGUAUGUGGCCCUGCGCAACAUCAAUCUCAUCGUGCAGAAAAGGCCUGAGAUCCUGAAGCAUGAGAUGAAGGUGUUCUUCGUGAAGUACAACGACCCUAUCUACGUGAAGCUGGAGAAGCUGGACAUCAUGAUCCGCCUGGCCUCUCAGGCCAACAUCGCCCAGGUGUUGGCAGAGCUGAAAGAGUACGCAACAGAAGUGGAUGUGGACUUUGUACGGAAGGCUGUGCGUGCUAUUGGCCGCUGCGCCAUCAAGGUGGAGCAAUCUGCGGAGCGCUGUGUGAGCACGCUGCUCGACCUCAUCCAGACCAAGGUCAACUAUGUGGUCCAGGAGGCCAUCGUGGUCAUCAAGGACAUCUUCCGCAAGUACCCCAACAAGUAUGAGAGUGUGAUUGCCACACUGUGUGAGAAUCUGGACUCCCUGGAUGAGCCUGAGGCCCGGGCUGCCAUGAUCUGGAUUGUGGGCGAGUACGCGGAACGGAUCGACAACGCAGAUGAGCUGCUGGAGAGCUUCCUCGAGGGCUUCCAUGACGAGAGCACACAGGUCCAGCUGCAGCUGCUGACAGCCAUUGUGAAACUCUUUCUAAAGAAGCCAACAGAGACCCAGGAGCUGGUGCAGCAGGUCCUCAGUUUGGCCACUCAGGACUCAGAUAACCCAGACCUGCGGGACCGUGGCUACAUCUACUGGCGCCUGCUGUCCACGGACCCGGUGGCAGCCAAGGAGGUGGUGUUGGCUGAGAAGCCACUCAUCUCUGAAGAGACGGACCUCAUCGAGCCCACACUGUUAGACGAGCUUAUCUGCUACAUCGGCACGCUGGCUUCCGUCUACCAUAAGCCUCCCAGUGCCUUUGUGGAGGGGGGCCGGGGCGUCGUGCACAAGAGCCUGCCACCUCGCACGGCCUCGAGUGAGAGCGCAGAGAGCCCUGAGACAGCCCCUACUGGAGCACCUCCUGGGGAGCAGCCAGAUGUCAUCCCCGCCCAGGGCGACCUGCUGGGUGACCUCCUCAACCUGGACCUCGGCCCCCCAGUGAGCGGCCCACCCCUGGCCACCUCCUCGGUGCAGAUGGGAGCUGUGGACCUUCUUGGCGGUGGCCUUGACAGCCUGAUGGGGGAUGAGCCUGAAGGGAUUGGGGGCACCAACUUCGUGGCACCUCCAACAGCAGCAGUACCAGCCAAUCUUGGAGCACCCAUCGGCAGUGGCCUGAGUGACCUCUUUGACCUGACCAGUGGCGUGGGCACCCUGUCAGGAUCAUAUGUGGCCCCCAAAGCAGUCUGGCUCCCAGCCAUGAAGGCUAAGGGGCUGGAGAUCUCAGGCACCUUCACCCGCCAGGUGGGCUCCAUCUCCAUGGACCUGCAGCUGACCAACAAGGCCUUGCAGGUCAUGACCGACUUUGCCAUCCAGUUCAACCGCAACAGCUUUGGCCUGGCCCCCGCCGCCCCCCUCCAGGUCCACGCGCCACUCAGCCCCAACCAGACAGUGGAGAUCUCCCUGCCUCUCAGCACGGUGGGCUCGGUCAUGAAGAUGGAGCCUCUGAACAACCUCCAGGUGGCCGUGAAGAACAACAUCGAUGUCUUCUACUUCAGCACCUUGUACCCACUGCACAUCCUCUUUGUGGAGGACGGGAAGAUGGACCGGCAGAUGUUCCUGGCCACAUGGAAGGAUAUUCCCAAUGAGAAUGAGGCCCAGUUCCAGAUCAGAGACUGCCCCCUCAAUGCAGAGGCUGCGAGCAGCAAGCUGCAGAGCAGCAACAUCUUCACUGUCGCCAAGAGGAACGUGGAGGGCCAGGACAUGCUCUACCAGUCCCUGAAGCUGACCAACGGCAUCUGGGUGCUGGCGGAGCUGCGGAUCCAGCCGGGCAACCCCAGCUGCACGGACUUAGAGCUGUCCCUGAAGUGUCGAGCACCAGAGGUGUCCCAGCACGUGUACCAGGCCUACGAGACCAUCCUCAAGAACUGAGACCCCGGCCAGCGCCCACCCCAGCCUUCUGCCCGCCCCAUCGAGGAGGCCCCUCGGGGGCAGCACAUCUUCCUCCUCGCAGGAGGGACCAGGCGGGGCUCCAGGCCACUCAGUGGGCUCCCUGGUCCUGAUGGCAGAACCCACCCGAUCCCUGGGGUAGGGCACCACCCCCUCCUGGGGUGAGAGCGCAGUGCACUCCCGUGCUCUGGGACACCCCUGCUCCUGUGGCUGUGAUGUGGGGUUAAGUGAGGUGGGGACCAAAGGAAACAGAGCCAGAGCAGCCACAGAAGCUGUGCCUGAAGGGUGAGUGUGGAGCUUGCCCCUCCGGCUCACAGCCCCGGCAGCCCCUGGCUCCUUGGUCUCUCCGGUUGGUGUUAAAGGGCCCUCCACUGCCACCUCUCAUGGGAUGGACCCUGCCAACCUGGCCUGGGUGUGCAGGGAGGGGUUCCCCUUGGUACCAGGAGAGCUGCUCACUUAGGGCCUGGGGCUCAAGGAGCUGUAGGUGCCGGCAGAGGGGCAGAGCUAGGCUGGGAGGAGCCCAGGGCCUGCACCACCCACUUGCAACCACCAGGCUGGUGCCCUGCAGCUGUGCCAGUUGGGCCACAGCCUCCCGAGUGCUGACCCACAUGGUCAAGACCAGGCAGAAGCUCCCAGAGCCCCUGUCUCGGGCUCCCCACCGACUGGCAGCUGCACUAUCCCCAACUCCCCACUUCUGCCCCAAGGGUGGUCACUGCCUGUGAUACAUUCCUCAGUGUCGCCUCUGAGCCCAGGCCUCCUGCCACAAAGACUGGGCCGAGAGAUGGGGCUGGGUAAGCGGGUGCGCCUCCUGUUUGGGUUUCUUCGGGGUUUCUCUGUAGUGUCUGCUGCCCUCCUCCUGGCCUCCCAGGUUUCAGUUGUGUCUGACAGAGCAUUAGGUUUUCCUGUUACUGCUGUGUAAUAAUAAAGAAAGAUUCGGCUUUUGGCAAUCACGGACACUUUUUUCCCCUCCACCGAAUGUCAGGAUUGAAAGCUGCCUCCGAGUGGUUGGGGAUGGUUUUCUGACCCUACGGUAACUAGAUCUAAUAUAUAUCAUCAGAAAAUAUAUAUUGUAUGUUUACUCUUAUUUUCAGAAAGAGAAAAUGAAUAAAAAUGAUGACAUCAA